AGGGCGAAACGCGGUGCAGAGGGAGCUGUGGGUGUGCACACAGGUGCCGGUCAUGUAUGAAUCAGACUUCCCUGGACGAAUGUACAGGAAGGAUGAGCCCUUUGCAUCUCUGGGUUAAAAAAAAAAAAAGUUAAAAAAAAAAAGGACAAGAAACUGGUGACCGCGGUCGCUACCGGCGAGGGAUUCUGUUUGUCCUGAUCUGUUUGAAAUUUUUACCAUUUGCUUAUAUGCCGUGUCUUUCCUCCACCCACCCGGACGACAGCAAAGCCAGCCCACAAGUUUGUUUUGUUUUUCCAUCGUGAUUCAGAUUUCUUUGGGGGAGAUUUGUUGCUGGUAAACAAAACAUCGUGUUUAUUUCCUCUCUUGCCAUGCAUUUGCCAAUAUAGAAUGUAGACUCUAUUAUUUUAAUAGAACAGUCUAGCUUUGUGGAAAACGAGAUUCGCAUGAAAACACACAGGCAUUUUCCAUGAAAAAGGUGUAAGUGGGGAAUGAUUUGGUCGAUAACGGUGUGUGCAUUUGCUCCUUCAUUAAAAGUGUUUAUUAAGUGCUACUUGUGGGCAGCGGUUUUGAGUAGACAGUUAUGCAAUCGUUAGAAGUGAGGAUUAUGAAGACUAAAUGGAAAAAUGCUUCCAGUUUGGACUUAAACGGAGAAAAUCAACAGGAUGCAAAUGGCUUAUGCGACAUGAUUACAGUUCUGAAAGGAAGAAGGCCCGGAAGUACACCAAAUCGUGACAGUGGCAUGUGGGCACAUUCCAUGACAGUACAGGAUUAUCAGGAUCUCAUAGACCGAGGAUGGCGAAGAAGUGGAAAAUAUGUGUACAAACCUGUCAUGAAUCAAACAUGUUGUCCUCAGUACACAAUAAGGUGCCGACCUUUACAAUUUCAGCCUUCAAAAUCUCACAAGAAGGUUUUGAAAAAAAUGUUGAAAUUUCUAGCUAAAGGGGAGGUUCCCAAAGGAAGUUGUGAGGAUGAGCCCAUGGAUUCCACAAUGGAUGAUGCUGUUGCGGGUGACUUUGCAUUGAUAAAUAAACUGGAUAUACAGUGUGAUCUUAAAACACUCAGUGAUGACAUCAAAGAGAGUUUAGAGAGUGAAGGAAAAAAUUCAAAGAAAGAAGAACCUCAGGAAUUACUUCAGUCACAAGAUUUCGUAGGAGAGAAGUUGGGCUCUGGUGAACCGUCACAUUCAGUUAAAGUUCACACAGUUCCUAAGCCAGGCAAAGGGGCUGAUUUGAGUAAGCCUCCAUGUCGAAAAGCAAAGGAAAUCCGGAAAGAAAGGAAAAGGUUAAAACUAAUGCAGCAGAACCCAGCUGGAGAACUUGAGGGUUUCCAGGCUCAAGGUCACCCACCAUCUUUGUUUCCACCAAAGGCUAAAUCCAACCAGCCAAAAUCACUCGAAGAUUUAAUUUUUGAGUCUUUACCAGAGAAUGCAUCACACAAGUUAGAGGUGAGGGUGGUGAGAUCAUCUCCACCAAGUUCGCAGUUCAAAGCCACACUUCUGGAGUCUUACCAGGUCUAUAAACGUUACCAGAUGGUUAUUCACAAGAACCCACCUGAUACGCCAACCGAAAGCCAGGUGAGGUUAGUACCUGUCUCCUUUGAGGACCCAGAGUUCAAGUCGUCUUUCAGCCAGUCCUUUUCUUUGUAUGUCAAGUAUCAAGUGGCCAUACACCAGGAUCCACCCGAUGAAUGUGGGAAGACUGAGUUCACAAGAUUCCUUUGCAGUUCACCCUUGGAGGCAGAGACUCCCCCUAAUGGGCCAGAUUGUGGCUAUGGCUCCUUUCACCAGCAGUACUGGCUUGACGGAAAGAUCAUUGCUGUGGGGGUGAUUGACAUCCUCCCAAACUGUGUAUCAUCUGUGUAUUUGUACUACGAUCCUGAUUAUUCGUUUUUGUCUUUGGGCGUCUACUCUGCACUACGAGAAAUUGCUUUUACUAGGCAGCUUCAUGAGAAAACUUCUCAACUCAGCUAUUAUUAUAUGGGUUUCUACAUUCAUUCAUGUCCCAAGAUGAAAUAUAAGGGUCAGUAUAGACCUUCUGAUUUGCUGUGCCCUGAGACAUAUGUUUGGGUACCCAUUGAGCAAUGCCUGCCUUCACUUGAAAACUCCAAGUACUGCCGUUUCAACCAGGACCCAGAAGCAGUGGAUGAGGAUCGCAGUACGGAACCUGACCGAUUGCAGGUGUUUCACAAGAGAGCCAUCAUGCCUUACGGUGUUUAUAAGAAACAGCAGAAAGACCCAAGUGAGGAGGCUGCUGUUCUGCAGUACGCCAGCCUGGUGGGGCAGAAGUGCUCCGAGCGGAUGCUGCUGUUCAGAAACUGACCUGUUCACCUCUGCCGGGAAGUUCCUGUGUUGUGCUGAUGAUUUGUGCCAGGAUACAUAUUCAGUACCUGUGGGGAAAUAACUGUCACCACCCACAAAUUAGACAUUUUUUAUUUUGACUAUCUAUGGCUUUUAAAAAAUAUUUUGUGGCAAUGUAUCUGUGAGAAUCUCAUAGUUAAUAUAAAGAUUUUAAAACUGCAUUAUGACCUAGCCCCCAUAAUUGGGAUUUAUCAUUUUGGAGGAUUCUUUCUAGAGCAAGAUACGCUCAAAUUCUCCUGUUUGUAUUUUGUAAAAUGAAGAAGUGAAUCUAAGUAACUUAAUCACAGUUGUGCAUUUUUUUUGGUUCUGUUAGAGAAAUUAAAACAGACUGUUUCCUCAGGCCCAUUUUAAACUGAACUUAUGCUAGGAAACCUUAAGUAUGGGGAAGGUAGAAAGUUCAUUUCAUCACUUAGAAAAUAUGUCUUCUCAAGAACAAAACUGUGCUGUUACAACUCAGUGUUCAAUGUGAAAUUGCUGCCAAAUGUUAUGUAGUUUAAUAGAGAACUUGAAAAAAUAAAACAUUAAAAUGGAGCUUGUGUUAGCAUCAGGUAUCCAUUUGUUCAGGACAGUCCUGUUCAUGUCUGUUGUCUUGGCAUAGUUUUUUCCCCUAGAAUAUAGUACUCCCUUUUACUCUAAAAAAUAUCCCAGUUUGGACAAUAAAAUACAUAAUUACUCUAGUUAUAUUAUUUGCUUUACUUCUAAAAAUGUAAGAAAUUGAAUUUUUUUAAAGAAAAAUGUUGGUUCCUGCCUUGAUCUAAGUCUCAUCCAAAGGAAAUAAAUAGUCACUAGUUUUUUAUCUUACAACUCAGGACAUUUGUCUUUGGUUAUUAAUGGAAAUUAGUAUGUGAUUACUUUCAUAGUUAUGCCACAAAUCACAUUGAAGAAGGAAUCAUUCCGACCUCUGUUCCAGGACAAGAGCUAGAACAAUCCAUUUCUUGUCCUUUGAUUUGAGAGUCACAGUCAGGGUGGCUUCUGCCACCCUUAGUAACUCAGAGCAGAGGCCAGCCCCCUCCUUCCCUCACUUUCUUUUGCUGAGUCCUUUGCCCACCUGUCAAGGUGGCAGGCACUGUGCUGGGUACAGGAGGACAGUCAGACAUGUCCCUUCUUAGCUAUAGUCGAGCUGUCUGGGAAACAGGAUGAAAAACAGGAGGGUUAUUUUCUUGUGCCCUCUUUGUCAGCUGAUCCCCUCUUCUGCUACCAGCUAUUUGGCCAGCAAGCCGUUUUUAGUCCCCACUUUGCCCAUUUUUCUGUUUUGGUUCAUCGUUUCUUAAAAGCCAUGUUAUAAAACAUGGUAGUUUGAAUCCUGUUGCUAAUUUUAAACUUUCCUCUAAAAUGUACUGAAUUUUGACAAAAAUUUGAAAAUAUCCUCAGCUAACUAGAAUAAAAAGGAUCAUAAAACAAUGAUUUUAAAACUGAAAUCUCUAGAAACUCAACAUCCAAGUCAGCCGCAUUUCUUCAUUCAGAGUGUGUGUGUCACACCUGCCAAGGUGCUGCGUACUCUGCUAACCGAGCUAGAGUAGUGAGCAAAGCCAUUUUCUCUGAUCACAAGAUUUUACAUUUUUCUGGGAUUUUGACCUGCAAAGUAGUCUCGUAAGAGCAUUUGAGAGACUUACUUGGAACUGCCUUCAGAAUCUAUAGAGCCUUUUUUCUCUUUUUCCUCUAAAAUGAAAAGAGCUUCAUUUUAUGAUUAUAACAAAAGUGACACUGUAAGCAGUUAGAACAUUAAGAAGUAUAAAUAAAAAGUAAAAAUCAUCUACAACCCUACCAUACUCAGAAGGAGAAAAGAACUGUCAUGUAUGUAUACACACAUACCUAUGUAAUUUUAAUAUAAAUAGAAUUAUGUUCUACAUGCUGUUUUAUUUCCUCAACAGUAAAUUAUGGACAUGUCUGAAAUGUGAAAUAAAUUUCAAAAUAAGGCUUCAGAAAGUGUAGUAAGUAAUCUCUGCAUUAUUAAAAAUAAGCAGGGUAGGGCUGGUACUUGGCUCGCUUAGCAUUUGAAUGUCCAACUUGGUGUUAUCACUGUAUCUUCCCUCCAUUUGUCUUUGUGAUUAGCAUGUAAAAUGGUAUUCAUAAAGAUCACAACCCUUGAAUAUCAGAUGAAGAGAAAACUUGACUCCAACAUCUUACCACAACUCUGGUUUCUUCCUGCAGAAUUCAUUUUCAGAGGAAAAUGAUGAAUCAUCCCUGUCUGUGAACCACUGUGCUUUCCUUGAGGGUGGCAUUGUAGGUUGACACCAGCAAAGACUCAGAGUGACUUGAGCAUUGGAGAUCCUUCUACUUGGCUGCUGUAUUCAUGCAUUAUGUUGGUUUGAGAAUAGCUAGUGUAUUGAUCCAAGUAGUCAAAGUGUCUUAAAAGGACACCUAUUUGUCCUUUUGAGCCCCAGCUGAGUGAAUACUGAUAGUGGACUAGAAAAGCAUAGUCAAGAAAAGUGACCCACCUUGUUACUUGACCAGCAGUCUAGCUGAGAGAUCUGAUUUUAUGUUCGUAACUUUCUGUAAAGAAAGACACAAGGACUUUUCAAAGACAGUUUAUAUCUUUCCAAGGCAGGAAGCUUUGCAUUUGCAAUCUUAGUGUUGUGUCCCUUUCUGAUUUUCAAAUACAUCACACCUGCCUUCCUGUUUUGGGAGCAAAGAUGUAAUUUCAAUUCCCCUUGCUACCGUCCUUAUUUAAAUUAUUUCCAUUCUAAGAGAUUUUUGUUAUUUUUUUAAAUGUAAUCUGAGCACUUUUUUGUAUUCUAAAAGAUAGAUGAUAUCAGAUAAAUAUGUUGUACAUUUGAUUAAAAUUAUUUAGAUAAAUAUUACUAUGUUGACUUUUAAAUAGCUUUAUCCUAUUUUUCAUUCAUUUUGCAAAUAUUUGUUGUGUGUAGUUUCUUAACGUGUCAGAAUCUAUUAUGUAAAAGAACCUUUCCAGAUUUCUGAACAGUAUAUGCUUUGAUUUUAUAGGCUUUAUAUUAUUUCAGUAUGAAUAAAGAUAAGGAAUAUGAAACAGUUAACUAAAAUGUAUCUGUCGUUGCUAACUUGAAAAAUGAAGUAGAAACAGUUGGAAAAUGUUUGAAUUAGAAGUUAUUCAAGUGCACACUCUUUUCUAAAAGAAAGCCAAUGACUAUAAGGCAAAAGAAGUUUGACUGCAUGUGGUAUUUUUUGCUCUUGUAUAUGCUUUUUGAACAAGCUAUUUGAUAAAGCCUGAAUGGAAAAAAUAAAGCUGUUUCUAUCUGCA